AGUAGUUCCGCCCGCUGGUCAUCGCGCCCUUUCCCCUGCCGGUGUCCUGCUCGCCGUCCCCGCCAUGCUGUCUCUAGACUUUUUGGACGAUGUGCGGCGGAUGAACAAGCGGCAGGUACAAUGAGAGAAAUGCAAAGAUAGUUAAGAAAGACUCGGCCUUCAAGGAGCCUAAAUGUGUAGAAAAGGACUAAGGCAAAACAAUAACUUUUUUGAGCUCUUGCCAUGUGUGAAGCACUUUAUACACCUGUAAGCUCUAUUAUCAAGUCCUAAAUUUUGGAAUGAUUGUCUCAUCGGCACUAAUGAUCUGGAAGGGGUUAAUGGUAAUAACUGGAAGUGAAAGUCCGAUUGUAGUGGUGCUCAGUGGCAGCAUGGAACCUGCAUUUCAUAGAGGAGAUCUUCUCUUUCUAACAAAUCGAGUUGAAGAUCCCAUACGAGUGGGAGAAAUUGUUGUUUUUAGGAUAGAAGGAAGAGAGAUUCCUAUAGUUCACCGAGUCUUGAAGAUUCAUGAAAAGCAAAAUGGGCAUAUCAAGUUUUUGACCAAAGGAGAUAAUAAUGCGGUUGAUGACCGAGGCCUCUAUAAACAAGGACAACAUUGGCUAGAGAAAAAAGAUGUUGUGGGGAGAGCCAGGGGAUUUGUUCCUUAUAUUGGAAUUGUGACGAUCCUCAUGAAUGACUAUCCUAAAUUUAAGUAUGCAGUUCUCUUUUUGCUGGGUUUAUUCGUGCUGGUUCAUCGUGAGUAAGAAGCCUGCCUUGCUGUUCCUGGGAAGAUGCCAUAGUUUUCGUUACUGGAUGUUUGGAGUAGAUACUGGUCUGUGAUUGGUGGAAUGGAGAACACACGUGUUGGUGCUUCUGGGUAGCACUGGUUUGCAUUAGUUUAUGUUUCCAUGCCAGAGUUUGUGUGGGCGGGCGCAUGUGCACCACAGAGUGCACUCGAGGGGACUUUCAGUCACAGGAUUUCAUAAUUGUCAUUGUCACACUUUCAAAUUUUUGUACAUCAGUGAAUUUUUUUAUAUUAAAAGGUUGAGCCAAAGCCCCCAGUGUUUGUAUUUUGAAGCCAAGCUUCACUUCUAAAGUGCCUACAGAGACUUGUAAAUGAAAAUGCAGCUCUGCACGAGUUUGAAACCGUCAUACCUCCUUCUAUUAGGAAUGGCAUAUACUGAGGUGGUCGUAAGUCUUAACUUCUAAAAUUUUAAAUAAAAGACUUUGCACAUUGAA